AAGGAGAAGCCGUGAUCUGGCUAUAUGGUGGGGCGCGGGCGGUGUCGCUGUGGGGAGCUGGUGCUGUUCUCAGGAGCCAGCCUGGAUCAUUUGUUGGCAGUACAUAUUGGCUGAAGUCAGUUUUCAUUUCAAGAUGUUUCCUUCCAAUGGGCUUUUGGUGUAGGAUGUCGGAGAACCAAGAACAGGAGGUAAGAGUAUGGUCUGCAGAGAACAGGAGGUGAUUACAGUGCGUGUUCAGGACCCCCGAGUGCAGAAUGAGGGCUCCUGGAACUCUUAUGUGGAUUAUAAGAUAUUCCUCCAUACCAACAGCAAAGCCUUUACUGCCAAGACUUCCUGUGUGCGGCGCCGCUACCGUGAGUUCGUGUGGCUGAGAAAGCAGCUACAGAGAAAUGCUGGUUUGGUGCCUGUUCCUGAACUUCCUGGGAAGUCAACCUUCUUCGGCACCUCAGAUGAGUUCAUUGAGAAGCGACGACAAGGUCUGCAGCACUUCCUUGAAAAGGUCCUGCAGAGUGUGGUUCUCCUGUCAGACAGCCAGUUGCACCUAUUCCUGCAAAGCCAGCUCUCGGUGCCUGAGAUAGAAGCCUGUGUCCAGGGCCGAAGUACCAUGACUGUGUCUGAUGCCAUUCUUCGAUAUGCUAUGUCAAACUGUGGCUGGGCCCAGGAAGAGAGGCAGAGCUCUUCUCACCUGGCUAAAGGAGACCAGCCUAAGAGUUGCUGCUUUCUUCCAAGAUCGGGUAGGAGGAGCUCUCCCUCACCGCCUCCCAGUGAAGAAAAGGACCAUUUAGAAGUGUGGGCUCCAGUUGUUGACUCUGAGGUUCCUUCCUUGGAAAGUCCCACUCUCCCACCCCUCUCCUCACCAUUAUGCUGUGAUUUUGGAAGACCCAAAGAGGGAACCUCCACUCUUCAGUCUGUGAGGAGGGCUGUGGGAGGAGAUCAUGCUGUGCCUUUGGACCCUGGUCAGUUAGAAACAGUUUUGGAAAAGUGAGCUCUGGGUUCUGCUCUGAGAUGGUCAGAGAAGAUGCGGGCCAGGAGACUUACUCAGGUGGGACUGGGCACAGGGCAGGUAUGUGGGAGGCUGGGCUGCUUAGUGUCUUCUAGUCACCUCUGCUUGGGCUGAUUGACAGAGGUCAGUCAUUACAGCCCCUUAUGCCUCUUCCAUGGGAACAAAUACUGUGCAGAUGUUUGUAAGUUAAACAUAAGACACAGGGGCUGUUGCUUUUGAACAGAACCCUAUAUUACUCUCCUGGGAUCUGAGUUUCUGCAGGUCAUUUGUAUGUAGGACCAGGAGUAUCUCCUCAGGUGACCAGUUUUGGGGACCCGUAUGUGGCAAAUUCUAAGCUGCCAUAUUGAACAUCAUCCCACUGGGAGUGGUUAUGUUGUAUCCCCAUCUUGGCUGGCUUCAGUUUUUGCUGUAGCCCUAGAGCACUUUGUUUGUGGGAGGCUGGCCUCUUGCCUACCUCCUUGCAUGGACAGGGGGAUGAAUAUUUACUUUCCCACCUCCUUGCUUUUUCUUUCACUGAUACCACUGAAUGGAACUGGUGCUGUGACUCCUGCUGCUGGGGAUUUAUGUCCCGAGACCUUAGCCUGGCUGAGUGGAGCCUGAGACCUGCACAACAGCUCAUGGUCAUGCAUGAGAGAGAAGUGGCUGGCCACAGCCAGAGGGAACAGUAACAGCCCAGGGGCCUUUAUUUUGGGAAAGGCUGUCCCGGGCUGUUACUGUCUCUUCUGGUUAUAAAGCAGACAUGUGGCCAUCUUUUCCGCAGGGUUAGAGUGGGCUCCUUUCUUUUUGGAAUCCUUUUCUUCUCCUUUGGUAGCAGCUCCCUGCCUCCAGGGCUUCCGCCACCAGCGUCUCUGCUGUGUUGCGCAGUGCAGUGGGGUGCAAGGGCUUUGUUUCUGCCUGCCUGAAAGAGAGGGCUCUGGGGAUGGAGAUGAGAAACAACACGCUCUCCUUCAGACAAUGAGGCAUUCUGUCCUCCUGCUGCCAUUCUUCAUCUCCACUGAGAGCCAGAGCUGGUAGGAGCCGAGUGCCACAGGCAUUCUGCAUUGCUCUACUCUUAGGUUUGUGUGUGUGAUCCUUCCCCUCCCUGUCGCCCACUCCUCCCUCCUCUGGCUAUCCUACCCUGUCUGUGGGCUCUUUUACUACCAGCCUAUGCUGUGGGACUGUCAUGGCAUUUAGUUCAGAGUGGAGGGGCUUUGGCCUGAAAUAAAAUGCAAGUAUUUAAGAUUGUUGUUGCAAUUUGUGUCUAACAAGCUGUAGCAGAGAAGGAGGGAGUGAGCGCUGGCAGUAUUUCCUUUCAUAAAUCAUGAAUUUAUCAGUGUGGAAAUAAUGCUUCAGAACUGUGCUCUGUAGCCCUCCUGCAUUGUGUGUGCAGCUCAAGUUCACCACUGGAGGAAGGAUUGUCUUCCAAAGAGCUGGGAUCCAACUCUUCUCACAGUUCUGGGCGUGAACCUUGUUAGGUAUAAUUUACCUGAUGCUGCUUCCAUCCUCGCAGUCUGUCUGAGGUGCCAGGUGCUGAAAGAGAAAUAAAGUUUGUCAACAGGCAGAUGCAAAGCCCUGGCUGGUAUUCAUCCCUCUUUCCUGCCCGCCUCCCCUGGGUCUCUCCUUUAUAUGAUGCAGCAGAGCAAGGCGAGGAUAGAAAACCUACAGAGGCAAAUCCAAAAUGUCAGAAGAAGUUCAUUUAAAAGGGGAAAAAAACUCCAUGUGCAACCCUCACAAAAACCCGACAGAUGCUAAGCUAAUGGCAUCCGCUCUGCCGAUUGGUGGGGAUGGCUCAUGAAUAUUAAUGAGCCCAAUGCUCCAAAUGGUGCAGCUGUGAACCCAGCUGUGCCUGAAGCUCUCUGAUCUCGAAACUUCCAGACAGGAGCUGGAGGUGGUCUGUGUCAAUUCCCUACUCAGCCAAAAAAACAGCAAGCUGGGUUGGCCUUCUUCUGUUUGCUCCUUUUCUUCCUGGAGUUGGUGCUCAGCAGCUAGUUCUGCCAGCCGGCUAGGCUGCUGGGACAGCAGGAGCCAUUCAAAGACAUGGAUGUGAUUUUUCUGACUCCCAGCUUUUUUAAUGAUCCAUUAGCAGCAUGCAUACA